GCCAUACCUUAAGUCUGGACCAUUUAUCCCUGUAGGGAGUCCCUCUUCUCCUCUGUUCUCUUUCAGAACUACUUAUUACUUUAGGUUCAGUGUAUGUAGCAUAUGGUGACUCUAUGGGUUUCAGUUUUCUGAACCCCAAAUAUGCAAAAAUAUAGAAAAAGCAGACCAGGCAUCCCACCUUCUGUGUGCCACUAAGGGAGCAUCUCUUCCUCUUUCUCCCCUAAUAAGUUGUAUAUUAUUUUCUCAGUAUUUUAAUUUUUUGCUAUUUAUAUUAUCUGAGAUUUAUCAUUGGAAUCAUACAAAUAUUAAACCAGGAAAGAUCACCCAGGAAGAAAUUGAGAUCACCCACAAUAUCAG